GUCCGGUGCUGAAGCUCGGCCCGGCGUCGCCGCAAGAGCGCGAGAGGCGCGGCGGGAGGAGCCGGCGGCGCGCGCCUCCCUGGGCCCGGACUCGGCCGCCUCCCGCCGCCUCCCGCGCGGCCAUGGACUGAGCGCCGCCGGCCAGGCCGCGGGGAUGGGGCCGCCGCUCCCGCUGCUGCUGCUGCUACUGCUGCUGCUGCCGCCACGCGUCCUGCCUGCCGCCCCUUCGUCCGUCCCCCGCGGCCGGCAGCUCCCGGGGCGUCUGGGCUGCCUGCUCGAGGAGGGCCUCUGCGGAGCGUCCGAGGCCUGUGUGAACGAUGGAGUGUUUGGAAGGUGCCAGAAGGUUCCGGCAAUGGACUUUUACCGCUACGAGGUGUCGCCCGUGGCCCUGCAGCGCCUGCGCGUGGCGUUGCAGAAGCUUUCCGGCACAGGUUUCACGUGGCAGGAUGACUAUACUCAGUAUGUGAUGGACCAGGAACUUGCAGACCUCCCGAAAACCUACCUGAGGCGUCCUGAAGCAUCCAGCCCAGCCAGGCCCUCAAAACACAGCGUUGGCAGCGAGAGGAGGUACAGUCGGGAGGGCGGUGCUGCCCUGGCCAACGCCCUCCGACGCCACCUGCCCUUCCUGGAGGCCCUGUCCCAGGCCCCAGCCUCAGACGUGCUCGCCAGGACCCAUACGGCGCAGGACAGACCCCCCGCUGAGGGUGAUGACCGCUUCUCCGAGAGCAUCCUGACCUAUGUGGCCCACACGUCUGCGCUGACCUACCCUCCCGGGUCCCGGACCCAGCUCCGCGAGGACCUCCUGCCGCGGACCCUCGGCCAGCUCCAGCCAGAUGAGCUCAGCCCUAAGGUGGACAGUGGUGUGGACAGACACCAUCUGAUGGCGGCCCUCAGUGCCUAUGCUGCCCAGAGGCCCCCAGCUCCCCCCGGGGAGGGCAGCCUGGAGCCACAGUACCUUCUGCGUGCACCCUCAAGAAUGCCCAGGCCUUUGCUGGCACCAGCCGCCCCCCAGAAGUGGCCUUCACCUCUGGGAGAUUCCGAAGACCCCUCCAGCACAGGCGAUGGAGCACGGAUUCAUACCCUCCUGAAGGACCUGCAGAGGCAGCCGGCUGAGGUGAGGGGCCUGAGUGGCCUGGAGCUGGACGGCAUGGCUGAGCUGAUGGCUGGCCUGAUGCAAGGCGUGGACCAUGGAGUAGCUCGAGGCAGCCCUGGGAGAGCGGCCCUGGGAGAGUCUGGAGAACAGGCGGAUGGCCCCAAGGCCACCCUCCGUGGAGACAGCUUUCCAGAUGACGGAGUGCAGGACGACGAUGAUAGACUUUACCAAGAGGUCCAUCGUCUGAGUGCCACACUCGGGGGCCUCCUGCAGGACCACGGGUCUCGACUCUUACCUGGAGCCCUCCCCUUUGCAAGGCCCCUCGACAUGGAGAGGAAGAAGUCCGAGCACCCUGAGUCUUCCCUGUCUUCAGAAGAGGAGACUGCCGGAGUGGAGAACGUCAAGAGCCAGACGUAUUCCAAAGAUCUGCUGGGGCAGCAGCCGCAUUCGGAGCCCGGGGCCGCUGCGUUUGGGGAGCUCCAAAACCAGAUGCCUGGGCCCUCGAAGGAGGAGCAGAGCCUUCCAGCGGGUGCUCAGGAGGCCCUCAGCGACGGCCUGCAAUUGGAGGUCCAGCCUUCCGAGGAAGAGGCGCGGGGCUACAUCGUGACAGACAGAGACCCCCUGCGCCCCGAGGAAGGAAGGCGGCUGGUGGAGGACGUCGCCCGCCUCCUGCAGGUGCCCAGCAGUGCGUUCGCUGACGUGGAGGUUCUCGGACCAGCAGUGACCUUCAAAGUGAGCGCCAAUGUCCAAAACGUGACCACUGAGGAUGUGGAGAAGGCCACAGCUUUCGCCACAGGCAGAGCUGCGUGGUCACGGUGGACUGCCCGACCCACAAAGCCUCCGACACUCACUCUCCAGCCCGUUACAGAAACCUUUUCUCAAGAUUGUAGAACAGCAGUUCUGCAAACGGGGCCCCUGAGCACCAGCUGGAGGUCGUUAAAAACGCAGACUCUUGGGCCCCACCCCAGAGGUUCAGAACAUGUCCUGGAGGCAAGGCCAGCAAGCCAUUGGGAGCAGCCCCCAGGGACCUCAAUGGCACUGGAGCCGAGUACCACUCACAGCUGCAGUCCAAGAGCUCCUGAAGACAAACCCCUGCCCCCUGCCAGCUGGGAGCUCCUCCACAGUAGACACUCAGCAAAUGCCUGCUGGCCGGAGCAGCGGCAGGGAAGGUAGACGACUGCAAGGCAUUGGAAACGGCCCCUCUGCAUCAGGAGACACCCUGGGUGCAGGAGGAGGCUUCGCUGAAAAGCAUUGCAACAGCAUUAUCACAUACGUGGAAAUAAGAAUUGCAUCUCAACCCUUCCCUUGCCCUCCACCCAUCUAACAUGCCUCAGCCCUCCUGUGGCCAUAGUAACCUGAACAGUAACUACAGCAGCAGGCUGCUUAGGUGCCAGGUGUAAGAAGAGAAAUUUCAUGAAAACAGGAAAAUAUAGCCUGCUUUUCUCCCCAGCUCUAACCUUUCAACCUAUAACUACUCCCUACUGUAAUUUUUGUGGGAUUUGCUGAUAUUGAAGGAAGAUGAUUGAAAAUCUGCUUAAGAUUUCGUCUUUAUUUCCCGCUUGACAGGCCUAGGGCCCCACUGAGGAAGUGUUUCUCUCUGCAGAGCCCUCAGCCACCCCAUAUGUCCCAGGGAUGUGCUCAAGUCACGAGGACCAGUCCUUUGUGUCACAUCCUGAGGUCCAGAGUCACCUGCCAGCCUUGCCGUCUGCUUGGCAUUAUUAAUUUUCCCAUAAAGUAUACAAUCUGGGUAAGGAUGUAUUCGUAAGGGACUUCACCAGGUGAGAGUCACCACAACUCAGGUGUCAGGUGUGUGUUUUCUAAAGCCGAUCUUAGCGUUAACGUUCUCCUGUAGGGAAAACUACUUUCUGUCUCUCUACAGUGCCUGGUUUUGGAAUUUCUCCACGGUGUUUUGUAAAUGUCUUGUGACACCAGCUGAAAAGGCUGUGUUCCUUUGAGCACUCAGAGCCCUUCCAUACUGAGGAGUUGGGAGGUGGUUGAAGGAAAGGAAGCAGCACAGCUUAGAGCACAUUCUGUGGCAAAACUGCCAGAGAGAGCCUGGGGUAGCCAUGCUGCAGGUCAGUGUGCCUGUCGGCCCUGGCCCUGAGCCUGGCAGCCCAUAUUUAGAGCCUCAUUUCAUCCUGGAGCCAGAAGGGUGGCUGUUUGCAGAGAAGGCCUUGAAUGGAGGGGACUCAUCCACCUCAUGGAAGGUGCCAUCCCAGGCUGGUGGUUGGGAACGGAGAGGGAGGCAGAGGGGGCACACCAUCUUGCUGACGGAGUCUUAUUUUUUGUGAUGCCUCCGAGCCUCAAGACCCCCAAGCUCACAGCCAUUCCUUGCUAGAGAAACAAAGCAGCAUAUUAUGUGAUUUUCAGAGGAAAUAAAUGGAAACAUACAACGUCAUGUCAGAGGGACGUGGGACACAUAGGUAAACUGAGGCAUGGAAAGAAAGCCCGUCCCUGUGUGAGGUUAGAGAGCCAGGGCAGGAUCUUUCCCUGAACGAAACUCUUUGCAUGCAUUCCUGCCCAUCCACCUCUUCCCUUUUAAAAACAUUUUCUUCAAGAAUUGAAUGGCCACAUAAUUUCUUAUUCUAAAAUAAGACAGAAAGACAGUGCCAUUCCCAUGCUCUGGGGUAAUUUCCAUUUUAAAUACGCAAUUUCUCCUCUUUUAAUAGAAGUCAGAUUUCUUUUAUCUGUAAUUAAAUCCAGAAUAUGGUUUUUUUUAAGGUCCUCGUGGAGUUUUGACUUUACUGUUCUGAAAAUGAAUAAGAGUUCUGAGCGUCAGUUUAGUGAACAACUCAACUCAUUAUCCGCUGGUUGUGAAAUACAAAACCUUGGUCUGACCCGUGGGGGCCGUGUGGUGGUGGCAGCCCCUGCCCUCCCCCCGGGUCUGAUGGCUCCAUCUGCCCCGCCAGCCACUGUCUUUCUGGCCGCAGCCCGUUAGCCCAGGGCCCUUUCAGCACUGACCUGAGACUUGGCUCUGACUUGGUCAGAUGACCAUGUGAACACAGCUGCUUCUGGAGGCCCAUAUUCCGCAAACCAUGCCCCUGCUCACUGCAGGAUUCUGCACGUUGCAUUUUGGAGUAAGUCUUCGGUAGACCUUACAGGACUCCCCCAUGAUCUUAUGUCCUUGGUUUUCAUGAAGGGUGCGAGGUAAGAAACUCAUUGAGAAAACUCACCUGAAGCUGCUGAGGAGGCUCCGCCAAGUCUCUCAGCCAGGACACGCCUGAGUGCAUCUUGGGGCCCAUGACCAGGAGAGACGUUGGUGUUCCUGGUGAACUGCAUGGUUCCUGCCACCAGACAGUCAGAGCCACUGCCAUGUCAGGCGUUUCUCUCGUCCCGAGUCGGCAAUCUCACUCCCAGAUUUUGUGCUCACCUGCUUAGCUUCUCUCACCCAGAAGUAUGCCAGAUUACAGUCAAUUACCAGAUGCGCAGCACCAUCUUUCUGCCUUUCUUCCCCUGGAUUACUUGUUUCUCAGCCUUGGUCUUUAUUAAGCUGAGUGUUUAUGCCUGCGCUGCCUGCAGCCCCUUUGGAAGCAGGUGAAGCAUCCAUCAUCCAUAAAAUUGGCCACUCUGUGCCCCAUCCCCAGGAGGCCCUGGCACUCCUUUCCCCAGGGACACCCGACAGCCCAGCAGUCAUCACAGAGCCACGCUGUGACUUGGAGGAGAAUGGGGUUGAGCCAGGAGUCAGUUCUGUUGCGGGGAGGGUGACCCUUUCUCUUCCCUCCCCUGCAAGUAGAAAAUGUCCCCCCCACCAGUCAGCUUCUGGAAAUCACUGGCACAGGGGGGGCUUUGGUGAGUGGGAGAUGACAGAGGCCCUGAGGAGAAGAAAAAGGAGCAUCUGGGGAGGAAGGAGUCCUUGGCGUCCCUCAGACACAGUGUGUAGAUGGCUCUCUUUUUAGCAGCCAGAUUCCAGGAAACAGCUGGACAGGAAACCAUGGGGCAGUGUCCGGCGUGACCAGUGUGUCCAAGCAACCUCACAGCGCUGGGCUCCCCAGGCUCCCCCGGCUCCCCCAUGGCUGUGACCCCAGUCUCUGGCCCCACAGCUCCCUCAUGCACCUCCCAUGCUCUCCCGGGGGCUGUGGCUGUCCUGGGCAUCUCGUCUUGGUCGUCUGGGUAACAGGUCCUGAGAGACGUCCCCAGGAGAAUGCUGUGCAUGUCCCGGGCUCUCCAGCUGCUUCUGAGCCCUGGACUUGGACACCCAGCACAUGUUCAGGUUGCCAGAGUCAAUGCGGUUAAACCCCAACUUGCUCGGGAUGCCUGUUUGUUAGAUGAACUAUGUGGAAUUCACCCCAGGUUUCUCUGUCCUCGUAUGUGGGAAGGUUUGUACUUAGAGGCUGAGACCUCGUCGCCUCUAGCAGCAGGCACAGGCCCCUGCAUGGCCACAUUCUGCUGAGAUGGUCCCUGCUGGUGGAAUUGUGGUAUCUCACUGAGCAUGUGUGUUGUCUUGCUGUAUGAGCCCGUGUCUCACUGUGUGUGUGAGUGAUUGUAUGUAGUGUGUGUCUCUCACUGAGUGUGUCUCACUUUCUGAGCACAUACAUAUGUGUGUAAGUGUGUAGAAUGGUCAUUAGCUAAUUGGUAUUAGGUUUUGUCGUGGUUGCCUUCUGGAAACUCUGUAGGGCACCCCAUUCCCUGACCUGCUGUGUCCAGAAUGGGUGGGUUCUUGGUCUCACUGACUUCAAGAAUAAAGCCACGGACCCUUGCA